AGUCUUCCGAGCAAGAUGGCGCCGCGGGCAUUUCUUCCACUGCCCGUCUGAGGGAACGCUAAGUAGUGUGUCCGGCGCCGUGUUCCAGGUAACUGGGCCACCGUGGCCGGGGAACGCAGACGCGCCACCACCUCCCGGCCGGCCCGGACCCUCAAUCUCCUCGGCGUCUUUGGAAGAUCCGAGGCCCAGGACUGGUGCCAGCUCCGCGUUGUUCCGCGAGAAAGCGAGAGGCCGAGCCCGGGCUGGUGCGAUGGCCGCGGUGGUGGCCAAGCGGGAAGGGCCGCCGUUCAUCAGCGAGGCGGCCGUGCGGGGCAACGCCGCCGUCCUGGAUUAUUGCCGGACCUCGGUGUCAGCGCUGUCGGGGGCCACGGCCGGCAUCCUCGGCCUCACCGGCCUCUACGGCUUCAUCUUCUACCUGCUCGCCUCCGUCCUGCUCUCCCUGCUCCUCAUUCUCAAGGCGGGAAGGAGGUGGAACAAAUAUUUCAAAUCACGGAGACCUCUCUUUACAGGAGGCCUCAUCGGGGGCCUCUUCACCUACGUCCUGUUCUGGACGUUCCUCUACGGCAUGGUGCACGUCUACUGAAAUGGGGGCCCGGGGGACUUUUUUAAAAAACCAGAUCGGGAGGACUGUGGCCAGCAAUUAACACCAUGUAGACUUCCUUAGUUCUUAAGUGGUUGAAUUCGCUGCUUGUUCUGUAACGUUAUAAAUAAUUUAUAUCUGAAGACGGAGAGCCUGUAAUAUUCUUCAGAUUAAAUGAAGCGUGAGACA